GUAGAGCUGCCGCCGUCGCCGCUGCCGCUGCCGCCACAGCCGCCGCUGCAGCCGGAGCAUCCGGGAGCCGCCACUGCCGCCGCCGCUGCCGCUGCUACCGCCACUAGCGCUGCUUCCACUGCUUCUACCUCCCCUCCCAGGACCCCGAGACACCCCGGGCGCGAGCGGCAGUGCUGCUUGCUUGCUCCUCCUCUCCCCCAGCCCUUCCCCUCCGUGACCUACCCACUCCUUGCAGCCCUCGCCCGCACCUUCUCCAACACCCCGGCAUCCCUGCACCACCUGCUCGGGCAGCCCCGGCGGGCUCUGGGACUUGCUGUGCGCGCCGAGAGGAAGGCAAGCUCCAAACCCCUGCCUGGAAGACGGGCUGUCGCGGCUGCACCACCAGCAGGAGGAGGAGGAGAAGAAACUAUUUCGCGAUACCCCAUUCUGCGGGUGCUUUGCCGCUGCCGCUUCUGCUGCCGCCGAUCCGAGUCCGCGGGUUCGAACACCGCAGCGGUGGGGACGGUGGGUCCGGCGGGCGCCGGGAGGAGGACACCAGCGGAGCCCUGCACUCUCGUGCCCCGCUCACCAGCAUCUACUUGCCCCCUCGUUCCUUCCCCAGCCCUUUAGAGAAGGGACCAUGAUUUGGAAACGCAGCGCCGUUCUCCGCUUCUACAGUGUCUGCGGGCUCCUGCUACAAGGUA